AAACGGCCAGCCUGAGGAGCUGCUGCGAGGGUCCGCUUCGUCUUUCGAGAGUGACUCCCGCGGUCCCAAGGCUUUCCAGAGCGAACCUGUGCGGCUGCAGGCACCGGCGUGUUGAGUUUCCGGCGUUCCGAAGGACUGAGCUCUUGUCGCGGAUCCCGUCCGCCGUUUCCAGCCCCCAGUCUCAGAGCGGAGCCCACAGAGCAGGGCACCGGCAUGGCCAAAGCCGCGGCGAUCGGCAUCGACCUGGGCACCACCUACUCCUGCGUGGGGGUGUUCCAACACGGCAAGGUGGAGAUCAUCGCCAACGACCAGGGCAACCGCACCACCCCCAGCUACGUGGCCUUCACGGACACCGAGCGGCUCAUCGGGGAUGCGGCCAAGAACCAGGUGGCGCUGAACCCGCAGAACACCGUGUUUGACGCGAAGCGGCUGAUCGGCCGCAAGUUCGGCGACCCGGUGGUGCAGUCGGACAUGAAGCACUGGCCUUUCCAGGUGAUCAACGACGGAGACAAGCCCAAGGUGCAGGUGAGCUACAAGGGGGAGACCAAGGCAUUCUACCCCGAGGAGAUCUCGUCCAUGGUGCUGACCAAGAUGAAGGAGAUCGCCGAGGCGUACCUGGGCUACCCGGUGACCAACGCGGUGAUCACCGUGCCGGCCUACUUCAACGACUCGCAGCGCCAGGCCACCAAGGAUGCGGGUGUGAUCGCGGGGCUCAACGUGCUGCGGAUCAUCAACGAGCCCACGGCCGCCGCCAUCGCCUACGGCCUGGACAGAACGGGCAAGGGGGAGCGCAACGUGCUCAUCUUUGACCUGGGCGGGGGCACCUUCGACGUGUCCAUCCUGACGAUCGACGACGGCAUCUUCGAGGUGAAGGCCACGGCCGGGGACACCCACCUGGGUGGGGAGGACUUUGACAACAGGCUGGUGAACCACUUCGUGGAGGAGUUCAAGAGAAAACACAAGAAGGACAUCAGCCAGAACAAGCGAGCCGUGAGGCGGCUGCGCACCGCCUGCGAGAGGGCCAAGAGGACCCUGUCGUCCAGCACCCAGGCCAGCCUGGAGAUCGACUCCCUGUUUGAGGGCAUCGACUUCUACACGUCCAUCACCAGGGCGAGGUUCGAGGAGCUGUGCUCCGACCUGUUCCGAAGCACCCUGGAGCCCGUGGAGAAGGCUCUGCGCGACGCCAAGCUGGACAAGGCCCAGAUUCACGACCUGGUCCUGGUCGGGGGCUCCACCCGCAUCCCCAAGGUGCAGAAGCUGCUGCAGGACUUCUUCAACGGGCGCGACCUGAACAAGAGCAUCAACCCCGACGAGGCUGUGGCCUACGGGGCGGCGGUGCAGGCGGCCAUCCUGAUGGGGGACAAGUCCGAGAACGUGCAGGACCUGCUGCUGCUGGACGUGGCUCCCCUGUCGCUGGGGCUGGAGACGGCCGGAGGCGUGAUGACUGCCCUGAUCAAGCGCAACUCCACCAUCCCCACCAAGCAGACGCAGAUCUUCACCACCUACUCCGACAACCAACCCGGGGUGCUGAUCCAGGUGUACGAGGGCGAGAGGGCCAUGACGAAAGACAACAAUCUGUUGGGGCGCUUCGAGCUGAGCGGCAUCCCUCCGGCCCCCAGGGGCGUGCCCCAGAUCGAGGUGACCUUCGACAUCGAUGCCAACGGCAUCCUGAACGUCACGGCCACGGACAAGAGCACCGGCAAGGCCAACAAGAUCACCAUCACCAACGACAAGGGCCGCCUGAGCAAGGAGGAGAUCGAGCGCAUGGUGCAGGAGGCGGAGAAGUACAAAGCGGAGGACGAGGUGCAGCGCGAGAGGGUGUCAGCCAAGAACGCCCUGGAGUCCUACGCCUUCAACAUGAAGAGCGCCGUGGAGGAUGAGGGGCUCAAGGGCAAGAUCAGCGAGGCGGACAAGAAGAAGGUUCUGGACAAGUGUCAAGAGGUCAUCUCGUGGCUGGACGCCAACACCUUGGCCGAGAAGGACGAGUUUGAGCACAAGAGGAAGGAGCUGGAGCAGGUGUGUAACCCCAUCAUCAGCGGACUGUACCAGGGUGCCGGUGGUCCCGGGCCUGGGGGCUUCGGGGCUCAGGGUCCCAAGGGAGGGUCUGGGUCAGGCCCUACCAUUGAGGAGGUGGAUUAGGGGCCUUUGUUCUUUAGUAUGUUUGUCUUUGAGGUGGACUGUUGGGACUCAAGGACUUUGCUGCUGUUUUCCUAUGUCAUUUCUGCUUCAGCUCUUUGCUGCUUCACUUCUUUGUAAAGUUAAGUUGUAACCUGAUGGUAAUUAGCUGGCUUCAUUAUUUUUGUAGUACAACCGAUAUGUUCAUUAGAAUUCUUUGCAUUUAAUGUUGAUACUGUAAGGGUGUUUCGUUCCCUUUAAAUGAAUCAACACUGCCACCUUCUGUACGAGUUUUUUUUUUUUUUUUUUUUUUUUUUUUUUUGCUUGGCGAAAACACUACAAAGGCUGGGAAUGUAUGUUUUUAUAAUUUGUUUAUUUAAAUAUGAAAAAUAAAAUGUUAAACUUU